GGCGGCGGGGAGCCGGGGAGAGCGCUUCUGCCGGCAGGUCCCCAAGCCUGCCCCGCGCCCAUAGGGACCGUAUUUUGCUUCUCGAUGCUUUCUUUGUGCUAACGUUCUGGGCGAACGCAGGCAGCAGCGCUGAAAAGGGCCAGAGUGGCCUGCAGCUCUGGGCUGCAGGGCAGAGAGCCCAGGCCCGUGGCUCGGGUGGGAGGUGUCCAUCCAGCUUGGCCCGAGCUUCGGUGGUCAGCGCGCAUUUCUCUUGAGGGUCAUCGGUGGUGACCUUUUGACUUUUUCACCCCACCCUCCCAUCUCUUUGUCUCGCAUUUGUGUUCCCGAUUCAGAGAUGGUAGAACCAAGUCCAUUUUAAAGUACCCUGAUGAACACUUUCCGUUUUUAUUUCUGAAAGUUCCCUGCUUGGUCUUUACUGCGAAUUUAAUAACAUGUUGACUACAUGGCAUUGUCCAGUGAUUACUAUUUUUACCUCUGAAAUCCAGCGAUCUUUCCAGUAGAAUUCUGGUCCGUCAGUCCAUUGUGUUUUGAGAUAAGCAUCCAGCAAGUACCUCCUUGGCAAUUAGAACAUCUGUUUUUUCAUUCAUUCAUUCAUUCAGCAGCUGUUUAGUACCGUACUCAGAUGAAGAGGUUUGGUGUGAAGGUAAAGUAUCCUUUCAUGGAAGAGGAUGCUUUGACUGAAGUAUAAUAGAUGGACCUUUAAAUGAGACAGUUACAUAAGUGAUGUCUGUUAAGGAAGGUAUGGUUAUAUUCUGGGUCAUUUUUUAAGCAGUAUAUCUGGAAGUUCAAGUGUAAUAGGAAGUAGAAUUAGAUUUGGUCUAAAUAUACAACAGCUUUUAUUUAUUUCUAAAUUUUAUUUUUUCCAGUCUUGCAGCCUUACAGUCAUUUGUAAUGGUUACCUCAGAUUCCCCUGCUGUGGUUAACGUUAAACCUAGGAGGUCAGAUGCUCUAAGUGAACAUGUUUAGUGCUGUGCCUGACAAAAGCAAGCAAUCAAAAUGGGACUUCCUUGAGGGCAGGCCUGUCUUGCAUCUGUUUCUCCACCACCUAGCCUGGAAUAUACUUCUUGGUGAAUUUUUGGAUGAAGCCAUUAAAUUAAUUGCUUGCCAUCAUGAGCAGAAGCAAGCGUGACAACAAUUUUUAUAGUGUAGAGAUUGGAGAUUCUACAUUCACAGUCCUGAAACGAUAUCAGAAUUUAAAACCUAUAGGCUCAGGAGCUCAAGGAAUAGUAUGCGCAGCUUAUGAUGCCAUUCUUGAAAGAAAUGUUGCAAUCAAGAAGCUAAGCCGACCAUUUCAGAAUCAGACUCAUGCCAAGCGGGCCUACAGAGAGCUAGUUCUUAUGAAAUGUGUUAAUCACAAAAAUAUAAUUGGCCUUUUGAAUGUUUUCACACCACAGAAAUCCCUAGAAGAAUUUCAAGAUGUUUACAUAGUCAUGGAGCUCAUGGAUGCAAAUCUUUGCCAAGUGAUUCAGAUGGAGCUAGAUCAUGAAAGAAUGUCCUACCUUCUCUAUCAGAUGCUGUGUGGAAUCAAGCACCUUCAUUCUGCUGGAAUUAUUCAUCGGGACUUAAAGCCCAGUAAUAUAGUAGUAAAAUCUGAUUGCACUUUGAAGAUUCUUGACUUCGGUCUGGCCAGGACUGCAGGAACGAGUUUUAUGAUGACGCCUUAUGUAGUGACUCGCUACUACAGAGCACCCGAGGUCAUCCUUGGCAUGGGCUACAAGGAAAACGUUGACAUUUGGUCAGUUGGGUGCAUCAUGGGAGAAAUGAUCAAAGGUGGUGUUUUGUUCCCAGGUACAGAUCAUAUUGAUCAGUGGAAUAAAGUUAUUGAACAGCUUGGAACACCAUGUCCUGAAUUCAUGAAGAAACUGCAACCAACAGUAAGGACUUACGUUGAAAACAGACCUAAAUAUGCUGGAUAUAGCUUUGAGAAACUCUUCCCUGAUGUCCUUUUCCCAGCUGACUCAGAACACAACAAACUUAAAGCCAGUCAGGCAAGGGAUUUGUUAUCCAAAAUGCUGGUAAUAGAUGCAUCUAAAAGGAUCUCUGUAGAUGAAGCUCUCCAACACCCGUACAUCAAUGUCUGGUAUGAUCCUUCUGAAGCAGAAGCUCCACCACCAAAGAUCCCUGACAAGCAGUUAGAUGAAAGGGAACACACAAUAGAAGAGUGGAAAGAAUUGAUAUAUAAGGAAGUUAUGGACUUGGAGGAGAGAACCAAGAAUGGAGUUAUACGGGGGCAGCCCUCUCCUUUAGGUGCAGCAGUGAUCAAUGGCUCUCAGCAUCCAUCAUCAUCGUCGUCUGUCAAUGAUGUGUCUUCAAUGUCAACAGAUCCGACUUUGGCCUCUGAUACAGACAGCAGUCUAGAAGCAGCAGCUGGGCCUCUGGGCUGCUGUAGAUGACUACUUGGGCCAUCGGGGGGUGGGAGGGAUGGGGAGUCGGUUAGUCAUUGAUAGAACUACUUUGAAAACAAUUCAGUGGUCUUAUUUUUGGGUGAUUUUUCAAAAAAUGUAGAAUUCAUUUUGUAGUAAAGUAGUUUAUUUUUUUUAAUUUCAAGUGAUGUAAUUUAAAACCUAAGUUGUGUUUCAAAACAGCAACAAAACUGUAUUGUAUUUUUUUUGCUGUAAUUAACUGUAUAAUGUAAACCUAAUUAUUUUAUCAUGGUUUAAAUUUUUUGCAUAUUUGCUUUAUCUUAUGCUGCUGAUUUUUUUAACUGAAUUUGUAAGAUUUUGUUUAUCAAAGCAACUAUUAUGUGGUGACUUGCCUAUAUCAUGAAUUAUUUAAGAUUUUUAUAGUUUUUUUUAAUUAGAAUUUAUUUCAGAUGUUUUGUUCAUGAUACUAUCCUUCAGGGUUAUGUGCUUAUCAAUGAAAUAACCCCAGAGGAGUGAGGGAAAAUAACUUGUAGCCAGUUAUAUUCAGGAAUAACUACUGUAAAUGAUGAACGUGUUAGGAGACCUCCAAUAUUUGCUACUUGCCAAUCCUAAUUUAGUUACAAGAAUUGGUAGGCAAUCCUACUUAAUUUUGGCAAAAGCCCCGUCAUCUAAAUGGCAGAAUAACUCAGAGCAUGUCUUUGAAGAUGCUGGGCGUCUACCACCACCUUAUGUCCCCACCCUACCCAACAAAAAUAAGUAAAAAGAAUAUGGUGUAUUCUACAAAUUUGUGGCAUGCUCAAAGUUUAUGAUCACAUAAAGGCAAGAGGAUACUUCAUGAAUAAUACAUUUCAAUGCAAAUAAACAGAUGGUUCACUUCUACUAGCUAUGAGCCUGUUUUUGUAUACACUGAGUUAAUCUACUCAGGCUGUAGGUCCCAGCAAUGUUCUAGAGUCUGGUCUUUCCCUUUCCUGCAGCUUCGGGUCCUUGGACCUUUCCUGUUUCCUAUUACUUGGAGUGUCUGUCAGUUGAGCACCAGUUGUUCUGGUGUUUCAUUUGAUUCUACUUGUAGCAUAAUCAUUUAUACGAGCUAUUGGGAGGUUCCAAACCCUACCUAGAUUUGUGUAGGUGAUGUAUCAAAUGAGCAAUAUACCGUUCAUCUGAAAAUAGUAGCACACAGCCAUAUAUAGGAUAUCAUUUUCUAAGGACUGUUUCUUCACAUUGAGCAGAGCAGGCAUAAAUGGUGGUUAUUUAGUCUAAGUCUUUUAUUUUUUUAUACCUGAUUUUCAACAUAACACGCAAUGUGGAUGUCGAGUAGUGUUAAGAAUGGUGCUGCUCCUGACAAGUGUAUGUUAACUGUUUACAUUUUCUAUCUGUAGAAUUAUUUCUCUAUUACUGAACUUUUCCUAAGUAAAAUGUCUUUGAAGUCUCGUUAUUUCUGAAAUACGUUGUCUGUAAUAGACCCAGGCACCUUUUAAAUUAUCUCUGGAACAAGAGGGAUUUCAUGUAAUGAACUAGGAAAUGCAUACUCACAUAAGCAACAAGGUUCUAGGCAGAAAGCCCCUUGGAAUUUGUGACCAACAGGAGCAAGAACAGGUGCGGCUCAACAUGCAAUGUCUGAAAAUUUGCUUGGCAUUUUAUUCAUAUAUUUAGUGCAAAAUUAUUUUUGAGUGAGAUAUUUUACAUCACUGUUAAUGUGCAAUAUUUAAGAUUAAAAUACAUUAGCUUUUUUAUAUACUUUGAAGUAGCAAGUUUGUUUUCGAUGGCUUAGAGUCAUGAUUUCCAGCUUCCCAGCCUUUUUAUCAGUCCCUUUUCUAAUACAACAAGGUGCAUUAAUUUGAUUAGGCAAAUUAGAGUUCUAAGACACUUCUUGAAUUGUAGACAGAAAAUAUUGGAUUCACAAUUUCAGCAGAAAUUUGAGAAUGAGUGUGUUUAUAUUAAUUUCACAAUUAGCUGUAUUUUCUGUAGCAUAGAUUAUGUCACUGUUGCACUUUCACAGCAGACAUGCUUUCAGAAGGUUCUCAUAUUUUAUGUUUGAUUGCUGAUAAGCCAUCUCUAUUGAUACAGAUUUUGGUUAAGUAAGGAAAACCAGGUGUGUGUCUGUAUCAUUUAUUGUAAAUGCCAGCUGCCACUUGCCAACCAUCAUGUUCAGUUCAAUUCAAAGAAAACAAACUCUCAUUACUUAGUGUAAACUAAAAUACUUAACAAAUUAUAUCCUAAAAACAAGGUCUCUUUGUUAAAUGUUGCAUGCCCUAGGUUUUAAAUUACUACAUCCAAAUACAGUUUUCGUCUUAAAUUUGUUAAGCUAAAUAUAUGUUGGUUCUUUUUAUUUUGGAAUCCUUUAAGCAUCUUAAACAUUUUUUUUUUGAAGAGAAGUUACAAAUAACAUUUCUAUCAGGUAGUACUUGUAUGAAACCACCUUUCUUAUUCUAUAAUUUUGAUUUUUCAAUUUUAUAUACUUAAUAUACUCACUGUCUUACUAUCAGAAAGUUAUUUUGACCAAGAUUUUUAUUAUCUUCAUAGAUUCAGAAAGAGAUGCUAAUUCUGUACCAAUGUCUUCCUGGUUACUAUUCUCUUCCCUCUAAUAUAUACUGGCCAUUUGUAAAACCAUUGUGUUGUUGGGAUCACUUAGUUAUACUAUACGCAGAUAGAGCAUCUCAACUCUGUCAUAGUGUUUGCUGAACAGUUUUCAGUGUCAUGCACCUUUGGCUGCUAAUUGUUCCUGACGUGCACUCUUCCGAGUUGGUAAAGGCACAGUGUGUUCAUGCCAGACUUCUAAGAGAAACACCAGCCUCUUAAAUCAGAAGCCUACACACAACCCCCUUAACAAUCCAAAGAAGCUUGAUGGUGUGCAAAGAAGCAUCCUGCCAGCCUUGUCAUUGUUCUGUUCUAUGCUAAUCCUGCUGUGUUGUCUAAAAGAUGGAGGGAAGAGGACAUCAGUGUCUGAUAGUGAAAUCAUCAGCAGGAAAGUGAAGCUCUUUCCUUGGUUACAGAUAAGACUUGGUUUACACUAUUGGCCAGUAUCUGCUAAACAUAUGAAGACUUAACUAUUCAGUGUUGCCUAGGCAUUCGCCUGCACAACAUUUUGAGGUUAGAACAUAGAAUAUUUUCAGAAAUACUGUUGUAGUUUGUGAGUGUUGUUCAUUAGUUACACAUUAGCUAUAGAGUGGAUGCAUGAAGCCCCAUGACACCAGUAAACUUCUCUUACCAGUAGGUAAACCAAACACCAUUCUGUCAUUAGCAGCCCUCUUAAAUGUUGCCUCUCCGUAUCCUGUUGCAUUUUUGUGUGCAUUGUGUUUCUACUGAUCUCUCUUAGGUUUUUACGGAAUCAAAGGAAACUAAUUUUUCCUUAAUAGCAAGAAAGAUGAAGAGGUAAAGGGCAUUGAAGCAGAAAUGUAUAGUUUGGGGUACGAUUAGAAAACUCGUAAGGAAAACAGAAGUCCUAAUUUCAAACUGACUGCUCUUCGUUAAGUGCUCUUAAGGAGAGUCUAGUAACAGUAACACUUUCUGGCCAUUUCUAGUUUAGAUUCUCUUCGUUACUGAAACUUUUGAGAAAUAUUACCUGUGGAUUAAUUUUGCACAAUGUUCUAUUCUCAUAAUGACUUACAAAUUAAACUAGGUUUUUAUUGAACUACCUCACACUAAUUUUCUAUGCUUUCCCAAGUAAGCUGUUGCCCUGUUAGAUCUUUACUGAGUGAAUUAUAAAUGUGUGUUAAAUACUUUCUAGCCAAUGUUGACACAAUACCAGUAAGUAUGUAAAGUAUAUACCUUACAUCAGUAAGAGACACGUGUAAAAUCUUUGACUGUAUGUCUUGCAAAAUUGUGCUCGUUGACAUUAUUACUGUUUUUGUAAGUAGAAACCUGCUCGUGAUAUCGGUCCAUUUACAUUUUACAAAAGGAGUAAAUCUUAGUAAAAAUUUUACGAAGAAAUAAAUUACUUUUGUAGGCCCAAUAUUUGGUAUAUUUUUGAGAAGCUGUUAAUCUUUUAGCUGAAUAAUGAAGUUAGACUGAAUUACGUGUCUCCCUGGACUGUGACAUCUAUUUUCUCAUUACAGUUUAUCCUGGUCAGCAGGGUGUCACACCUGGAAACCUGAGUAUGAUAGCUGACAUUUGCUUUUCUCCCUCUGCGAUGUCAUUCCUCCUCCAUUCCUCUCCUUCCCUGUGUUCCGUUCCCUCUCCUUUCCUCUAGACAAAACAAAAUGGGGCACUUUUUAGGGAAUGCUGAGAUCAUUAUUGUGGUUUUUCAUCAUUCAUGCCCUAGUCAUUAAACAUGCACCACUGGAAUGUAAACAAUGUUAUCUAGUAUGUCAAUUGGUUAUAAUAUUUUAAAUAAAAAAGAAAAAAGUGGUAUGAAAAUUAUGAAA